GAUUGUGGGAUAGUGGCGGAGGGAGCCGGGCGUCGGAGGCCCUGAGGCCGGCCGCAGAGCCCGGAGAUUGAGCGGCUUUGGGGAAGGGGUGGUUAAGGAAGUAGGCCUCGGCUUCCGUCGGUCGCUGCUCGGCUCUGCGGCCCGUUUGGACCGCGGAGGAGGUCGCCUUCCCCUCCCGUGGGGCGCUCGGUUGGACUGUGGAAACCGGGGCAACUUCCCCCGUCUUCCCGGCUGAGGCGCCUGCGUGGGCCUCGCGACCCGGCUCGCCAACCCGCCUCGGCCCGCACGCCCACCUCGCCUGCGGACCCCGGAGGUGCCUACGCGGACUAGUGACGCCCCCCGCCCGUCGGCAACUCCACCCGGCGCUGACCCCCUCAACUCUGCAGGACCCGGCGCGCGAGGACCCCACGACCCGCGGGCGCCUGCGCGGACCCCGCGAGCCCCGGCGCCUGCGCGAGUCCCCGACGCCGCCCCCGCCCCCACUCACCGGGCCCCGCAGCAGGGGCCGGAGCCGCCGGCGGCGGGGCGGGGGGGGGCGCCCCGAUGAGCCCCGAGUGCGAGGAGCCGCCGCCCCCCCUCGCAGGGCGCCAUGUUUUGGAAGUUUGACCUGCACACAAGCUCGCACCUGGACACGCUGCUGGAGCGGGAGGACCUGAGCCUGCCCGAGCUGCUGGACGAGGAAGACGUGCUGCAGGAGUGCAAGGUCGUCAACCGCAAGCUGCUGGACUUCCUGCUGCAGCCACCCCACCUGCAAGCAAUGGUGGCCUGGGUCACCCAGGAGCCGCCAGAUAGCGGUGAGGAGCGGCUGCGCUACAAGUACCCCAGUGUGGCCUGCGAGAUUCUGACCUCAGAUGUGCCCCAGAUCAAUGAUGCCCUGGGUGCUGAUGAGUCCCUUCUGAACCGGCUCUACGGCUUCCUGCAGAGCACCGGCAGCCUCAACCCACUGCUGGCCAGCUUCUUCAGCAAGGUCAUGGGCAUCCUCAUCAACCGCAAGACAGACCAGCUCGUGUCCUUUCUUCGGAAGAAGGAUGACUUCGUGGACCUGCUGCUGCAGCACAUUGGCACCUCGGCCAUCAUGGACCUCCUGCUGCGCCUGCUCACCUGUGUGGAGCGGCCUCAGCUGAGGCAGGAUGUUGUCAAUUGGCUCAACGAGGAGAAGAUCGUCCAGCGGCUGAUUGAGCAGAUCCACCCGUCGAAGGAUGAGAAUCAACAUUCCAACGCAUCCCAGUCCCUGUGUGACAUCAUCCGCCUGAGCCGGGAGCAGAUGAUCCAAGUCCAGGACAGCCCAGAGCCUGACCAACUGCUGGCCACCCUGGAGAAGCAGGAGACGAUUGAGCAGCUCUUAAGCAACAUGUUCGAGGGGGAGCAGAGCCAGUCUGUCAUCGUCAGUGGGAUCCAGGUGCUGCUGACCCUGCUGGAGCCCAGGAGGCCGAGGUCCGAGUCCGUGACCGUGAACAGCUUCUUCAGCAGUGUGGAUGGGCAGCUGGAGCUCCUGGCCCAGGGGGCCCUGGAAAGCACUGUGUCCAGUGUGGGCGCCUUGCACGCCCUACGCCCGCGGCUCAGCUGCUUCCACCAGCUCCUGCUGGAGCCUCCCAAGCUGGAGCCGCUACAGAUGACAUGGGGCAUGCUGGCUCCGCCUCUGGGCAACACGCGGCUGCACGUGGUCAAGCUCCUGGCCAGUGCCCUGAGCGCCAAUGAUGCAGCCCUGACGCACGAGCUCCUGGCACUGGACGUGCCCAACACCAUGCUGGACCUCUUCUUCCAUUAUGUCUUCAACAACUUCUUGCAUGCCCAAGUAGAGGGAUGCGUGAGCACCAUGCUGAGCUUGGGGCCACCUCCUGACAGCAGCCCUGAGACGCCCAUCCAAAACCCUGUUGUGAAACAUCUGCUGCAGCAGUGCCGCCUGGUGGAGCGGAUCCUGACGUCCUGGGAGGAGAACGACCGUGUACAGUGUGCGGGAGGCCCUCGGAAAGGCUACAUGGGUCACCUGACAAGAGUGGCCGGUGCCCUGGUGCAGAACACGGAGAAGGGGCCCAAUGCAGAGCAGCUGCGGCAGCUGCUGAAGGAGCUGCCCAGCGAGCAGCAGGAGCAGUGGGAAGCCUUCGUAUCGGGGCCCCUGGCGGAGACCAACAAGAAGAACAUGGUGGACCUGGUGAACACCCACCACCUACACUCCUCCAGUGACGAUGAGGACGACCGGCUCAAGGAGUUCAACUUCCCUGAGGAGGCUGUGCUGCAGCAGGCCUUCAUGGACUUCCAGAUGCAGCGCAUGACCUCUGCCUUCAUUGACCACUUCGGCUUCAAUGAUGAGGAGUUUGGGGAGCAGGAGGAGAGUGUGAACGCACCUUUUGACAAGACAGCCAACAUCACCUUCUCCCUCAAUGCUGACGAUGAGAACCCCAACGCCAACCUACUUGAGAUAUGCUACAAGGACCGCAUCCAGCAGUUUGAUGAUGAUGAGGAAGAGGAGGACGAGGAAGAGGCCCAGGGCUCAGGGGAGUCUGAUGGAGAAGAUGGCGCCUGGCAGGGCAGCCAGCUGGCCAGGGGGGCCCGUCUGGGCCAGCCACCUGGUGUCCGGAGUGGAGGCAGCACAGACAGUGAGGACGAAGAAGAGGAGGACGAGGAGGAGGAGGAAGACGAGGAGGGCAUUGGCUGUGCAGCCCGUGGAGGGGCCACCCCUCUGUCCUACCCCAGCCCUGGCCCUCAGCCUCCAGGCCCCAGCUGGACAGCCACCUUUGACCCAGUGCCUACAGAUGCCCCGACCAGCCCCCGAGUCUCCGGGGAGGAAGAGCUGCACACUGGGCCUCCAGCCCCACAGGGGCCCCUCAGUGUGCCCCAGGGCCUCCCCACUCAGAGCCUGGCCAGCCCUCCUGCCCGUGACGCCCUGCAGCUCAGGUCUCAGGACCCCACACCCCCCUCAGCACCUCAGGAAGCCACAGAAGGCAGCAAAGUCACGGAGCCCUCAGCCCCUUGCCAGGCCUUGGUUAGCAUCGGGGACCUUCAGGCCACCUUCCACGGGAUCCGUUCUGCCCCCAGCUCCUCGGACAGUGCAACCAGAGACCCCUCUACCUCUGUCCCAGCCUCCGGGGCCCACCAGCCCCCCCAGACCACAGAAGGGGAGAAGAGCCCAGAGCCCUUGGGGCUUCCCCAAAGCCAGAGUGCCCAGGCCCUCACGCCUCCUCCGAUACCCAAUGGCUCUGCCCCGGAAGGGCCUGCAUCCCCAGGCUCCCAAUAGCUGCCUGGUGCGGCAGCGGCGGCCAAAUCUUCCGUCCUCCCGUGGAUCUCCCGGGGUGGGGGCAGGGCGGGUCCCACGAUGGCCCCCAUUGCCCUCAUCACCCUGACACCCCCACAUUCUCUCCUCUGGACCCCCAGGAGGCUGGUGCCAGGGAGACAGGCCCAACCCACCCCCAUUUGCACUGAGAAGAGAAGUUUUGGAGCGUUGCCUCCUAGAAUAAAGAUACAGAGAGUCAAAUAGAGAGAAUGGAGAGAGAGAAACAUAUAUUAUAUAUUAUAUAGAGAGAGGGAGGAGAGCGAGAGAGAGUGAGGACACCGAACUGGGCUGGCGGCUCCAAAGCACAGCCUUCCCUGUUCCGUCCCAGCGGGAGCUGGUGUUAGGGGUCCCAAGGUUGCCACCCACGUGCCCAGCUGUCCCACGCUGCAGCGCAGACGGCCACGCCCACACCCGGCCUUUUAGCUCAGGUCCACCAUGGGGGACGGCCCAGCGUGGGUGGGGGUGCCAGAGGGUCCCGAGUGGGGGCCGUGCCUUUGCCCAGACCCUGCACUUUCAACCAGGCCAGUCCGGCUCUGGGGAGCAGGGGCCUCCCCGGCAACAGCCCCAGGGGCCUUGAGGGUCUGAGGUCCCAGCCCUGUUGCCAAGUGACCUUGUCCCCAGCUCCCUCCUCCCAGGCUGGUGUGAGUGUGCGUGCGUUUGUGCCGAGCUUCUAUUUCAUAUUGCAAAUAUAAAUAAAGGAAGGCAGUUUACGA